CUUGUUGCCGGAAGUGGGAAGAGAGAAAGGUUGUGAUGGCGGCUAUAGCUGCAUCCGAGGUGCUGGUGGACAGCGCGGAGGAGGGGUCCCUCGCUGCGGCGGCGGAGCUGGCCGCUCAGAAGCGCGAACAGAGACUGCGCAAAUUCCGGGAGCUGCACCUGAUGCGGAAUGAAGCUCGUAAAUUAAAUCACCAGGAAGUUGUGGAAGAAGAUAAAAGACUAAAAUUACCUGCAAAUUGGGAAGCCAAAAAAGCUCGUUUGGAGUGGGAACUAAAGGAAGAGGAAAAGAAAAAGGAAUGUGCGGCAAGAGGAGAAGACUAUGAGAAAGUGAAGUUGCUGGAGAUCAGUGCAGAAGAUGCAGAAAGAUGGGAGAGGAAAAAGAAGAGGAAAAACCCUGAUCUGGGAUUUUCAGAUUAUGCUGCUGCCCAGUUACGCCAGUAUCAUCGGUUGACCAAGCAGAUCAAACCUGACAUGGAAACAUAUGAGAGACUGAGAGAAAAACAUGGAGAAGAGUUUUUCCCAACAUCCAAUAGUCUUCUUCAUGGAACACAUGUGCCUUCCACAGAGGAAAUUGACAGGAUGGUCAUAGAUCUGGAAAAACAGAUUGAAAAACGAGACAAAUAUAGCCGGAGACGUCCUUAUAAUGAUGAUGCAGAUAUCGACUACAUUAAUGAAAGGAAUGCCAAAUUCAACAAGAAAGCUGAAAGAUUCUAUGGGAAAUACACAGCUGAAAUUAAACAGAAUUUGGAAAGAGGAACAGCUGUCUAAUCCCUUCAAGAACUGUUUAUAGAAGCUUGAGAAUGGGGUAAAAAUUUCUGCUAGCAAAAUCAAGUUCUUUUUGAAAUUUUAUCAGUAAUCCAGAAUUUAGUAGUCCAUGCCUUCUCACUCAGCAUUUAGAAAUAAAAAUGUGGUUUCUUAAACGUAUAUCCUUUCAUGUAUAUUUCCACAUUUUUGUGCUUGGAUAUAAGAUGUAUUUCUUGUAGUGAAGUUGUUUUGUAAUCUACUUUGUAUACAUUCUAAUUAUAUUAUUUUUCUAUGUAUUUUAAAUGUAUAUGGCUGUUUAAUCUUUGAAGCAUUUUGGGCUUAAGAUUGCCAGCAGCACACAUCAGAUGCAGUCAUUGUUGCUAUCAGUGUGGAAUUUGAUAGAGUCUAGACUCGGGCCACUUGGAGUUGUGUACUCCAAAGCUAAGGACAGUGAUGAGGAAGAUGGCAGUGGCCACCGGAGGACUGGAGCAGUCCCUCCUCAUGGCGGCCUGUGACCAAGGUCGGGGAGGAGUGGAGCUAUCCUUCCAUGAUCUGAUCAUGUACAGUUCCCUUUUUAAAAAGCAAUAAAUGCUUGGGAUUAGAAUUUCUAACAUUUUUAGUCUAUCAUUUAAAACAAACAUUUGUAUAUAUACAUUUGUUUAUAUACAUACAUGCUUCCAUUCUACAAACACUGAAAGAAUAUUUUAUUAUGGGAAAUUCCAUACACCCAAUACCCCUGGUGAGUCCCAUAUACCCAGUACCCUGUUCAACAAUCAUUAACUCAUGGCCAGUCCUGCUUCAUCUUUAUUUCCAUUUACUUUCUUCAUGACUCUUAUUUUGACGCAUAUACUAGAUAUAUAAUUUCAUCUAUAAUUAUUUUAGUAUGUAUCUCUGAAAGAUAAAGACUUAAAUGACCACAAUACUAUUAUCACUGCAAUAGAUUUAUUUUUAUAAAACUCCAGAGGGAAAGGUUGUUAUUUUUUCUCUAUGUUGAAUUAAAUGCUAAAUAUCUAA